GGGGAUGGGCCGGUCCGACCCUUGCGUUCUGCCUCCCGCCCCGCCUGCCUGCGGCGACCCAGGCUGCCGACUGUACUUGUGCACAGCCCCGUCCUGAGGCCCCCAUGUGGUCGGAGCCCACGAGACACCUGCAGAGGACCGUGUGGUCGUAGGAGCCUGCAUGCGUGACCGCUGCACGUGUACACCCACACAGAACCCUCAUCACUGGGAAUUCCUGUCUUCAGCGUAUCCUGUGCUGGGGUCGGGAGGGGCUGGCUUGGUCCCUUGGCCUUUCUGAACUUCAUUACCUCUCCUAGGGGCCCGGACACCCUAGGCGAUGGGAUGAGGGAGAGAAGGGAGACUCUGGCUCUGGCCCCUGAGCCAGAGCCCCUGGAGAAGGAAGCUUGUGAGAAGUGGAAGAGGCCCUUCAGGUGAGGACCCAGGUGACAGUCUCAGAGCUCUGAGCUGAGCCCCACCCCAGAGGCUGCCAGGGUCUUCCUCUUGGACCUUGGAGCCAGCUCUUGGGUUGGGAGGGGGCUUGAGGAGAGGCCAGAAAGCUCAGAUCUCCCAGGGCUAGUCUGACCUCCAUUGUCUGGAGCCACUUGGGGUCAGUUCCAUCUCACCCCCCCAACCCCUACCCUCAACCCUUUCCCUCCUUCUUGGGAUCAGAGCUCUGGGGGUGGGGAGUCAGGCUUCUGAAUAGCUGUCACCAGGAGAGAACCUGUGGGCAAAGCCCAGAGCCCAGUCAUGCCAGGCAUGUGUGCGCAGCCAUAGGUGUGCAAGCAUGUGCAUCCGCAGGGACAUGAGGCCACAGGUGUGUACAAGCUUGACUGAGCCCGUCUGUAUGUGUGAAUAUAUAAGCAUGUGUAGAUGUGUGCUCACACUUGUGGGACCUGAUUGGGGCUUCAGACCUUGGGUGCCUGUCCGCAGGGUCUCCUCCAUCCUUCUUGAUUUGCCUGUCAUUGAGGCUGCCCGCUCUGGGCGCCAUUCCCCAGCCUAACACCUCUUCUCAGUCUUUCCUUGCAGGUCCCUGGUGUCCAGGCCUUGGGGCAGUGAAGAAACCGUGGGGAGGGGCAUGAGAUGCCAGUCCCCAAAGUCCUUGGGAGCCCUUGUGGGCCAAGUCAUUGUAGGACACACCCUCUCCUGGGCAUUGCUGAGGUCACCCAGUGAGCCUAGGCUCCCCCCUCCUCCCAUCCCCAGCCUGGGGGAACCUUCAGCGUCUCUCCUCCCUGUAGGCCCCGGCUCAGCUUCCCAGGAACUUUUGUUGGUCUGCCUCAGCCACCUCCCUGACGCUGUCCCACUGUGUGGAUGUGGUGAAGGGGCUUCUGGAGUAAGUGUGUGUGUGCCUGUGUGUGCACCCACGUGUGUGUCGGGCUCCCCAGCCCAGGCUUGGUCUGUGUCUGUGCCUCGACCUGUCCAUCCCUGUGAUGUGCAGCUGUCUGCCUGUGAGUCUGUUGGGCCUUGGAGACAGGAGCCAGGUGAAUGGCCUCAGCCCCGGCCCCGGUUCAGCUGUCUUCCAGGUUCUGUCCUCACAAGGGUCUGUCUUCAUCCAAGGUCGUCACAGGGGACCAAGAGCUCCAGCCUCAGGCAGGGCAGGAGCUCCUACUCAAUUGGGAAAAAUGCUCUGAAAUGUCAGGGACUCAUUCAGAGUCACAGAGCCAAGCAGUGGCAAGACUGGGAUUGAAACCCCGGCCCUGAGGUUUCUUUGCACCCACCAACCCUACCCUGCUCCUGUGUCUGCCUCUGUGUGCUCCCCACCCCGUCUCCACACCAACCCCUGGGGUCGAGGCUGGGUUGGGGAAUGCUCUCGCUGCUCCUUGGGGCCAUGUUCUGCCGCCUGCCAUGUCUGCUUCCUAUGGUUGAUGCCUCAGGGGAGCUGGAGGCUCCCACCUGAGAAGGACUUGCUGAAUGCCCUCCUGACCCCAACCCACCUUACCCCAGUUUUAAGAAGAGGAGAGGUCACUCAAUUGGGGGAGCCCCUGAGCAGCGAUACCAGAUCAUCCCUGUGUGUGUGGCUGCCCGACUUCCUACCCGGGCUCAGGAUGUGCUGCAGCCUCCUGGCCACUGGAGGGGCUGACCGCCUGAUCCACCUCUGGAAUGUUGUGGGAAGUCGCCUGGAGGCCAACCAGACCCUGGAGGGAGCUGGUGGCAGCAUCACCAGUGUGGACUUUGACCCCUCGGGCUACCAGGUUUUAGCAGCAACUUACAACCAGGCUGCCCAGCUCUGGAAGGUGGGGGAGGCACAGUCCAAGGAGACACUGUCUGGACACAAGGAUAAGGUGACAGCUGCCAAAUUCAAGCUAACGAGGCACCAGGCAGUGACUGGGAGCCGCGACCGGACAGUGAAGGAGUGGGACCUCGGCCGUGCCUAUUGCUCCAGGACCAUCAAUGUCCUUUCCUACUGUAAUGACGUGGUGUGUGGGGACCAUAUCAUCAUUAGUGGCCACAAUGACCAGAAGAUCCGGUUCUGGGACAGCAGGGGGCCCCACUGCACCCAGGUCAUCCCUGUGCAGGGCCGGGUCACCUCCCUGAGCCUCAGCCACGACCAACUGCACCUGCUCAGCUGUUCCCGAGACAACACACUCAAGGUCAUCGACCUGCGUGUCAGCAACAUCCGCCAGGUGUUCAGGGCCGAUGGCUUCAAGUGUGGUUCUGACUGGACCAAAGCUGUGUUCAGCCCGGACAGAAGCUAUGCACUGGCAGGCUCCUGUGAUGGGGCCCUUUACAUCUGGGAUGUGGACACCGGGAAACUGGAGAGCAGACUACAGGGACCCCAUUGCGCUGCCGUCAACGCCGUGGCCUGGUGCUACUCCGGGAGCCACAUGGUGAGCGUGGACCAGGGCAGGAAGGUUGUGCUCUGGCAGUAGGGCCACGACCUGCCUGCCUGGGCUGGAGCUCUUGCCCGAAGCCUGAAGCUUCCUUCGGCGCCAUGCAGGGGUUGGGGUUGGGACUGGAGCUGGCCUUGGGAUUUAAUGGGGAAGAAGGCCUGGCAGGACCUGGCCUGUUUGUUUAAAAAUGAAGUAUGGGUUGGGGGAUUACGCUAGUUUUUCUUUGUAUUUUUAUCUCUAUCUCCUCACUUUUUCUCCCAAAGUAGAAAAAAAUGAUAUCUGAA